UGUUGGAUGUGUGAGCACUUGAGGCUGGAGCGGGUGAGUGGCCGUGUCAGCUGAUAAUAUGGUCCUGGAGGGAACCCGGCUGGGGUCUCACACUCCCAGCAGCGGGCACCAUCAGAUGGAGGGGCCUGGCUUCGGCCUAGUAACCAGGCUAGAUAAAAAGUGAUAUUGUGUCCUGCAGAGAGAGAGCCUGCCCCACCCCACCCGCCAGGCCGUGCUCAUCGGCCCUCCUGGUGAGGAAGCCCACGUCCAACCCUGCUGGGCACCUGCCUUCCACAGAGACUUAGUGGCUAUUUACCUAAAGAGAUUAUUGAAGGAAUUUUCAUUUUACUCAGCCAUGAGGACAAAGGGUCUUAUUGAAACUGUUCUAAUAGGCUUAUGCCCAGUCACGGGUCUCUCAGGUCACAUGAGCGGUGGAGGCGGGAGCGGCCGUAUCCGAAGCAGUUUCCUCCUGGAGCUGUGGGGUCCUUGUCCAUAAGGCACAUCUGCACAGGAAGAGCCUGGAAAAGCGCUCUCACAGGCUGCCGGCCCAGCUGGUCACCCCGACACCCCAUCCCAGGGCCCUGGGCCUGCUCACCUGCCCAUCCCAGCCGCUGACCCCGUCCUCUGCUCCCACAUGGCUGACGCUCGGCAUGCCUCUUGUUCCCUGUGUCUCCUGGCCGGAAGCCGGACCCCAACCCUCCCAGACCCUAGAAUUGUGAAACUGAUGUGCAGCUGAGGAGUGUGCUAUUGGGACAGUGGAGGUGCUGCCCUUCCCGCGUGCCCAGCUCAGAGCACCGUGCGGUGUGAUUGUGUCUCGUCCCACGGCCAGCACUGCUAACCGCCAGGCUGGGUCACUUUCUAGGCGAGGACAGGGUCUUGCCCUGGCUCCGGCUGUCGGUGGCGGGGCUGGGGCUGGAGCGGCGGAGCCAUCUCCUUGACCCCUCAUGAAAUGCCUUCUGCUCCUGGCCAGUCCGUCCCUCUCCCUGCCACCCACUGACCAGAUGGCAUCUCUGCUCUUAGUGGAGGGCCACUGUCCACCGCCAAGGUUAUUUAUAGGGGUGAGCAUUAUGUGUGGCGUUUCCCUUAAAAUAACAAAAUAAGAAAAGUCUCUAGAGCAAAAAUGUUUAAAUCCCAUCUGCCUGCCCUCUCAUGUUGUACAUUAACGGAUUAAAAAGUAGAUUCCAGAAAUUAAGCCAUUCCACCAGGCCUUGGAUAUCAUCAGAGGGACGAUGGGUGCAGGUGCUCUGCGCACCUGCCACUUGGUGGGGCCCCCGAUCUCAGCCCCUCUGGCUGCAGGAGAGGCCCGGGGAGAGCUUCAUCACGCCCUCCCUCCUGGGGCCCGACAAGAACUUCACGCGGGAGCAGGCACGUGGGCGCCGGGGUGCAGGGGCAGCCACCAGUAGGUGGGCGGGGAGCAGCUUCGGGGGCAAGGGAGGCCCAGCCUGCCAGGACUCGCCAGCCCCUGUUGUUGCCAGGCUUGUGUCUAGGAAGUUCACGUAAGUGGUGUCUUGUGACCCAGCUUUCGCAAGUUGCUCUCCUGCCCAAUCUGACUUGAGAGACGUUCCACGUGGGUUCGAGGCUGUUCUUAAGCUGCGCCUCCUGGGUUGAACUACAAGGUGCUUAUCUGCUGCUUUGCUGGAGGUGAUUAGGGGAUUCCGGCUUCUCCCACUGCAGGUGAUGGCUGCAGGUAGAGCACGAGCUGGCAGCCUCAGGCAGUGGGCCUUGACCCAGCUGGCCCGGGCUGGCACUUCCAGUUCACUCCUGGGGCGAAUGCUGCUUCCUCUGCAGCCUGCCACGGGCUGCCCACGUUCCCCUCACCAGCUCGGGUGGGCUGCUGAGCGCCGGCCGUCUGGCCGCUGUGAGGAGCGUGGUUUCCUUUGCUCACAUUUGCUCUGCCGCCAUUUCUCCCGCCGUGGGCCAGUGUUUCCUGGCAGCCCUGUGGUUGCUGUCCUCCUCGGACCUGGUUCCCUUUUCUGCCUCCUGGGGACCCCGUGCCCUUGGGAUUGGACUGGUUGUGUGUUACAUACGGUGUUUCUCUGGAGUCAUUUUGAAUUUGGCCAAAUUUCCCUCCAGGGUUUCUGCUUUGAGUGUCAGCUGAGAGCGCUUUCCCCGGCCGAGUCCGUGAGGUGCUCCUGGGUGCACUGAGGUUGCCUGGGCCCCCGCUGGAACUGUGCUGUGUGGUGGGAGCUGCAGCCCCCGCCCUCCUCCAGGGAGACCCCCCGGCCCAGGACCCUGUGCACAGCAGUCCCUCCUGACCUGCGGCCCAUGCCCCGUCCCCAGCCAGCCCCUGUUGGGUGCCCUUCUGUGGCAUCCAGUCCUGCUGCCCCACGCCUGGCCCUGCCCUCGCGUCCUGCCUGCCUUCGGGCCUUGCCCACCUUCCCGCCUCCCUGUUCAGAGAAGCCGCCCUGAGGCCGUCUGGACGUAGAUUUGGGCGCAGCUGCCUGCACUCUGCCCAUUCAGCCUGGACCCCAACCAAGACCUGUGGAGAGCAGGGCCGACGCUGGGCUCAGGCAGCAGGAGGCUGUCCUCGUGUCAGAGUCGUGGCCGCCUGACAGAUGCCACCUCCCUGCUGGGACCGUUGUGAGGGCCCCUCCCCCAGCAGCCUUGUCACGAACGAGAUCACGCCGGUGCUGUCGUACUCCUACCUGGCCGUGCUGGUGCCCGUGUUCCUGCUCACCGACUACCUGCGCUACACGCCGGUGCUGCUGCUGCAGGGGCUCAGCUUCGUGUCGGUGUGGCUGCUGCUGCUGCUGGGCCACUCGGUGGCGCACAUGCAGCUCAUGGAGCUCUUCUACAGCGUCACCAUGGCCGCGCGCAUCGCCUAUUCCUCCUACAUCUUCUCUCUCGUGCGGCCCGCGCGCUACCAGCGUGUGGCCGGCUACUCGCGCGCUGCGGUGCUGCUGGGCGUGUUCACCAGCUCCGUGCUGGGCCAGCUGCUGGUCACUGUGGGCCGAGUCUCCUUCUCCACGCUCAACUACAUCUCGCUGGCCUUCCUCACCUUCAGCGUGGUCCUCGCCCUCUUCCUGAAGCGCCCCAAGCGCAGCCUCUUCUUCAACCGCGACGACCGGGGGCGGUGCGAAACCUCGGCUUCGGAGCUGGAGCGCAUGAAUCCUGGCCCAGGCGGGAAGCUGGGACACGCCCUGCGGGUGGCCUGUGGGGACUCAGUGCUGGCGCGGAUGCUGCGGGAGCUGGGGGACAGCCUGCGGCGGCCGCAGCUGCGCCUGUGGUCCCUCUGGUGGGUCUUCAACUCGGCCGGCUACUACCUGGUGGUCUACUACGUGCACAUCCUGUGGAACGAGGUGGACCCCACCACCAACAGUGCGCGGGUCUACAACGGCGCGGCAGAUGCUGCCUCCACGCUGCUGGGCGCCAUCACGUCCUUCGCCGCGGGCUUCGUGAAGAUCCGCUGGGCGCGCUGGUCCAAGCUGCUCAUCGCGGGCGUCACGGCCACGCAGGCGGGGCUGGUCUUCCUUCUGGCGCACACGCGCCACCCGAGCAGCAUCUGGCUGUGCUAUGCGGCCUUCGUGCUGUUCCGCGGCUCCUACCAGUUCCUCGUGCCCAUCGCCACCUUUCAGAUUGCAUCUUCUCUGUCUAAAGAGCUCUGUGCCCUGGUCUUCGGGGUCAACACGUUCUUUGCCACCAUCGUCAAGACCAUCAUCACUUUCAUUGUCUCGGACGUGCGGGGCCUGGGCCUCCCGGUCCGCAAGCAGUUCCAGUUAUACUCCGUGUACUUCCUGAUCCUGUCCAUCAUCUACUUCUUGGGGGCCAUGCUGGAUGGCCUGCGGCACUGCCAGCGGGGCCACCACCCGCGGCAGCCCCCGGCCCAGGGCCUGAGGAGUGCCGCGGAGGAGAAGGCAGCACAGGCACUGAGCGUGCAGGACAAGGGCCUCGGAGGCCUGCAGCCAGCCCAGAGCCCGCCGCUUUCCCCAGAAGACAGCCUGGGGGCUGUGGGGCCAGCCUCCCUGGAGCAGAGACAGAGCGACCCAUACCUGGCCCAGGCCCCGGCCCCGCAGGCAGCUGAAUUCCUGAGCCCAGUGACAACCCCUUCCCCCUGCACUCUGUGCUCCGCCCAAGCCUCAGGCCCUGAGGCUGCAGAUGAGACUUGUCCCCAGCUGGCUGUCCAUCCUCCUGGUGUCAGCAAGCUGGGUUUGCAGUGUCUUCCAAGCGACGGUGUUCAGAAUGUGAACCAGUGACUCUCGGGCGCCCCUGUGGUAACUUUGCAGGCGGCCCUCAGUGCAUCCCCACGACCCCUGCCUCGAGGGCCGCCUGCCUUAGCAAUGGGGGCCUCCGCUUAUCCUGCUAGCAGGCCCCCUAGGAUUCCCCCUGCCCUGUGCCGCACUCUGGCGGUGGCCACAGCGUGCUGGCGACACUCAGGGCAGCUGCCUGGCCAUGCUGUCCCUGCACUGUGCCCCGCGGGCUUUGUUGCUGGAAGAGGUGGGUGGUGGGCUUCUGCGUCCACCAGGCCUCACUGGCUCAUGCCCCUUGGGGGGCUUGAGACAAAUCCUUUCUGCCCCCCAGGGCUAGUGAAGUGGCCUCUUGGAUACCAGCUCAGGGGACACUGGCCCCACAGGAGUUGUGAGCCCUCUAGGGCAGGGUGGGAGCCGGGACCCUCAGGUGUAGCUGAGCUGUGACAUUGCUGGUCAUCCUUGGUGCUCUUGCUUUUUUGAAAGAUGCUUUUUUUUUUUUUAACUGACGUAGAAUGAAGAACUGCAUGUGGCUUCUCUGUCUCUGUGGAAAAGCCAUCUCAGGUUGGCGGCAGACACAUUGUCAUCAGAGGGGAGCAGCGGCUCUGGUCCUCGGAGCUGGUUCCUCUCUCCCACCCUAAGGGCAGCCCUCCAUGGUCCUGUCUGUCCUUCUGAAGUGUGUCCAUCCUGACCUGCGGGUCCUCAGCUGCUCCCACACUUGUGCCAGCCCGGAGGGGACUGGUCCCGGUCACCGCGGACGUGCUGGCCUUGGUAUGUGCCAGGCUUGCCUGGGCUGGGCAGCCUUGGGGGGGCUGCCUUUGUGGUGGGCGCUGGGGAAGUACGUCCCAGCGGCCUCAGGGUCUAAGGAGCGCUAGUGCCUUGCCCACAGGUGCGGGACCAUCUGAUGUGAUGUGAAUACUCUUCCCACAUACAUUAAACACACUUAAGUGAGUGUGCGCAGGGCUUCUGAUUCAGGGCCGGCCUGGCCUGGGGGUUGAGGGUCAGCAGUCAGUGAGGAGGCCAGGAGAGGCGUCCCAGCCUUCUCCCGCCUCCAGCCCACGCAGGGCCUUGGUGCCCAUGAGCUGAGCACCCCCACAACCCUAGUCAACGGCCCUAUCCUGUGGGGCCUCUGCCACAUCUCAGCGGCCCCAGGUGAAUGGCUGGCUGCUCAGCACGGAGAGCUGGGGAGAGAAUCUCUGGCUGGGGAGGGGCUGCUGGAGCUGCUGGACCCAGGGGUCUCCCGAGGUGGCUCAGGGGAGCAGGCAUCUUGGGGUACCCUGGGUUGAGGCAGAGGCUGCACGUGGAAGAUGGCCCGAGUCAGUGGAUGGUGCCAGUCAGACAGGGCCAUGGUCCCAGGUGCAUCCAGGGGCUCUGUCAUGGCCACCCUGGGGACCCUGCUUGGGGGGGGGUCUGCACCAGCCAUUUCCUGGGCUCGUAGAUCUAGCAGGAUGUGAUGGGUGGAGGUGGGCUGGGCCUGUGCCAUGGGCUAGAGCGUCACUGGGGAGGCCCACACCGCCAUCAGAAUCCUCCUCCCAGCGCCUCCCCAACCUGAGGGCCUGCUCCCUCCGCAGCCUGCUCACUGCACCCACUGCCUGCCUGCCUCUGAGUCCUGCACUCACCCGUCCACCAGGACAGGGAUGGCUGUCAGGAUGUAGUGUUGCUGGGAGCAAGUCAGGUCCUGCUGUGAGGAGAGACCUAAGAGUGUUGGUGUGUGUCCACACACCCGUGCAUGCCUGUGUACCUGUGCACACUAUGGAUGCUCCUGCACACCUGUGUACAACUGCACGCCUGUGUAUGGCCAUGCAUGCAUACCCCAUGUAACCGUGCGUGCCUGUGCACACUCGGGAUCUGCCAGUGGGGCAGUCCAGGGAUAAAAGACUCCUGAGAACUCCUUUUGGAGAAUUGUGUCCUUCCUGUGACAGUGAAGGCUGCUUGCAAACCAAGAGUCAGUGUAAAAGGUCACUUUUAUUUGCCUGUCUGAAUUGGCUUCACAUCACACACAAUUACAGAACCAGCCCCACCGGUUUCGUCGCAGUCCUGAGGCAGGUGCGUGUUGGCUGUGCUGUGGUCAGCCUGGCGCUGCCCUGAGUCCACUUGUCCCUCCACAGAACGAAUGACUCGGGUUGAUGUUGCCGGAUCUCAGGGGUGGCUGUGACUGACAGAGGACCUUGUUGCACCUCGUGGCUGCUUUGUUCACCCGCAGGGCGGCCUGUGGGCACCCCGGGGUUCCCCUUCAGUCCCAAGGAGGGUAAGGAUAUGGGUUUCCUAGGAGACAGCCAAUGACUGCCCUGCAUCUGGAGCCAGCCUGUCCAUGGGCAGUGCACAGAUGACAGCCCUCCCUCACUGCCCUGUGUGCUGGCUACCGCAUGUCCUGUGCCAGCCUCAGCCUCUUUGAUGUGGCCGUGUUCCAUCCUGGCGCUCAGCUGGACAAGUGCUGGCUGAGCCACGUCCCAGCCAGGGGCAUGAGAUGGGGGCCCUGGAUGGGAGGCUGCCAGACCCCAACUCAUGGGUCCCUUGAAUCUCCCAGCUUGGACUCGGCCAGGGUGGAGCUGUCUGCUUUGGAUGUAUCAUCUCAUGGCUCAUUUGGGAGGCCAGCCCCAGGCUGCUGUGCUUGGUGUUGGAGGACAGGCCGGAGCUGGGGGUCACAGUGCGCCUCUGAGCUUGGGAACCUGCUUCAGCCUGGGGUUGCUGUGGAGAAUGGCCCAGAGCUGAGCAGAAGGGGCUCCCCCUAGCCCCAGGGACCUGAGCCUCCCUCCCAUCUACCGCAGGGCGAGCACACACCCUGGAGGAGCCCAGAUGGCCUUGUGCUGAGUGUGGCCUCAGCUCCCAUUGCCUCACGGGGCCUGUCUGCUAACAGGUCUGGGUUUUGUGCACAGAACGGUGCUGCUAGGUGGGAGAUGAAGUCAGCACCUGCUGGGGCGAGCACGGCUUCCCAAAGCAGGAAAUCCUGGAGAAAUCGAGCCGUGGUCUGAUCAGGCCAAGAGGUUGCACAGGGCAUGAUACUGCACCCUGCCUGACCCAGCUGGGCUCACAGGUCAGGGGAGAGUUGGGGCAGGUGAAUGUCAGCAUCAGGCUUCUGUUUUAAACUUUUAAAAAAAUACA